AGAAGAGCAUGUCAUGGAGAACUCUUGGGUGCAGACAAGUGGAUGAUUAAUGAAGUAGCAUCUGAAAAACCCAAGGAACCAAAUGUAGGUGGAGCAACUUCCCUGCAACACACGUCGAAGCUGCUGCAGUGGCUGUUCUUCCCCUCCCCUUGGAAAGGCACCAAAAGCCAGCCUUUGGAAGGGCUGGUGGACUGUGCCCUUCUUUCCCUUCAGAGAACCAGUGUCCCUGUGACUCCACCCACUCAUCUGGCCACCGUUGCCCUGACCUGCCAGGAGCCUGGAGAAGAUGAAGGCAUCCGUGGUUCUCUCCCUCCUUGGCUACCUGGUGGUUCCAAGUGGUGCUUACAUCUUGGGGCGUUGCACAGUGGCUAAGAAACUCCACGAUGGAGGCCUGGAUUAUUUUGAGGGCUAUAGCCUUGAGAACUGGGUGUGCCUGGCCUACUUCGAGAGCAAGUUCAACCCCAUGGCCAUCUACGAGAACACACGUGAGGGCUACACUGGCUUUGGCCUCUUUCAGAUGCGUGGCAGUGACUGGUGUGGCGACCAUGGCAGGAACCGCUGCCAUAUGUCAUGUUCCGCUUUACUGAAUCCUAAUUUAGAGAAGACAAUUAAAUGUGCCAAGACCAUUGUAAAAGGAAAAGAAGGGAUGGGAGCAUGUCCCUUCUCAGAAGUAAACACUGGGAGCCAUAGAAGACACCACUGUAUCUUCACCCUUGGUUUGCUAUGAAGAUGUGACAAAGAAUGAGGAAGACCUACAUGUGUUCCUAUGGAGUGACUACAAUACAUGUUGUCAGAUGGAAAAAAUCAAGCUGCAGAAUAGUGUAUAUCGUAUGUUACCAUAUGUAAAAGAAAGGUGGAGAAAUAAGAACAUAUACACACAUAUGUUACAUACACAUAUUCAUUUGCUUAGUUUUACAAAAAGAAACACUGGAAAGAUAAACUAGAAACUAAUAAAAAUUGUUGCUCAUGGGAGGUGGAAUGGGAAAAGUGAAGGAGGGGAUACGAGUGGAAAUGAGACUUCUCUGAAUAUGGCUUUUCACAUAAUUUUGACUUUGCAUUCAAAUUUUACAUAUUCACAAAAUAAAUUAAAUCAAAAAGAAAGAAAAGACAAACUUGAAAAUUGAAAACAUAUCAGGCUUGGCUAAAGGAACCUAAUUGCGUACCAAAUUAGUAACACAGAUAUGACGAGAAAAGAAAAAAAUUCAGACAUCUCUGAUACAGUUCUCUGGUUCUAGUCCUCUGUGAAAAAUAUUCCAAGAGUAAAAAAAAAACUGCAUAUAAAUAUUUA